CACUCACCCGGACAAGUCGCGGCCCUUCCAAGCCUCACACUGCUUUCGUAGGAUCAAUUCCGAAUACCCAAACUCGGAGAUAUCACGAGGACUCCCCCGGGCCCCCAAACGCACCUCUCCUCUGGCUGGAAUGGGAGCCUCCAGAAGCAGUGCGAGACCACGGCCAGCGACAGAGGUCCUGGCGCUGGCGGAAUGACGCCAUUUUUGUUACUGGUAGAGCUCGGCUUCGUGGCUGUUUCGGAGCCACCGAAAGAUAAGCUCCCUCGUCACCCUGACAUCUCUCCGGGAAGACUGGAAGGGAAAUGGCCUUUCGGGGGAUGUUGAACGCAUUUGGGCAGGCGGGGAGCCAAGCCCGGCUUGAGAGCAGAGCCGGGGACGAAGUUCCGGAAAUGGAAUUACCGAGUCAGAUGAGAAACACAAGUCAUCAAUGAAUUAACAAGCAACACAUUGUCACAUCCAGCUGUUGAAGAGUGGUUAACUCAGCUUGAUCUCCGAAGACUCUUCUGCACCCCACCCCGCCCCCAACUGCUUUCCAAAGAGAAACAGAAAAUGAUUGAGUCCCAGGAACCAGUGACAUUUGAGGAUGUGGCUGUGGACUUCACGCAGGAAGAGUGGCAGCAGUUGAAUCCUGCUCAGAAGACCCUGCAUAGGGAUGUGAUGCUGGAGACCUAUAAUCACCUGGUCUCCGUGGGGUGUUCAGGUAUAAAACCAGAUGUAAUCUUUAAGUUGGAACAUGGAAAGGACCCAUGGAUCAUAGAGAGUGAGUUGUCAAGGUGGAUCUACCCAGACAGAGUGAAAGGCCUUGAAUCUUCCCAGCAGAUCAUUUCUGGAGAACUUUUAUUUCAAAGGGAGAUACUAGAAAGAGCCCCAAAGGAUAAUUCAUUGUACUCUGUUUUAAAAAUCUGGCAUAUUGAUAAUCAGAUGGAUAGAUAUCAAGGAAAUCAAGACAGAGUUUUGAGGCAGGUCACAGUCAUCAGUCGUGAAACAUUGACUGAUGAGAUGGGUUCCAAGUACAGUGCAUUUGGGAAAAUGUUCAAUCGGUGCACAGACCUUGCUCCUUUAAGUCAAAAAUUCCAUAAGUUUGAUUCAUGUGAAAAUAGCUUGAAGUCUAAUUCAGACUUACUAAAUUAUAACAGGAGCUAUGCAAGAAAGAACCCCACUAAGAGAUUUAGAUGUGGGAGACCACCUAAGUAUAAUGCUUCCUGUUCUGUGCCUGAGAAGGAAGGCUUCAUUCAUACUGGAAUGGAGCCCUAUGGAGAUAGUCAAUGUGAAAAAGUUCUCAGUCAUAAGCAAGCCCAUGUUCAGUAUAAGAAAUUUCAAGCCAGAGAGAAACCCAAUGUUUGUAGUAUGUGUGGGAAAGCCUUUAUCAAGAAGUCACAGCUCAUUAUACAUCAAAGAAUUCAUACUGGAGAGAAACCAUAUGUAUGUGGAGAUUGUAGGAAAGCCUUCAGUGAGAAAUCACACCUCAUUGUGCAUCAGAGGAUUCAUACUGGGGAGAAACCCUAUGAAUGUACUAAGUAUGGAAGAGCAUUCUCCCGGAAGUCACCUUUCACUGUUCAUCAGAGAGUCCAUACUGGAGAGAAACCCUAUGAGUGUUUUGAGUGUCCAAAAGCUUUCUCCCAGAAGUCACAUCUAAUUAUACAUCAGAGAGUUCAUACCAGAGAGAAGCCCUUUGAAUGCAGUGAAUGCAGGAAAGCCUUCUGUGAGAUGUCUCACCUUUUUAUACACCAGAUAACUCAUACUGGGAAGAAGCCCUAUGAAUGUACUGAAUGUGGGAAGACCUUCCCUCGGAAAACACAGCUCAUUAUACAUCAGAGAACGCAUACUGGAGAGAAGCCCUAUAAGUGUGGUGAAUGUGGGAAAACUUUCUGCCAACAGUCCCACCUCAUAGGACAUCAAAGAAUUCAUACAGGAGAAAAACCUUAUGUGUGUACUGACUGUGGGAAGGCCUUUUCCCAGAAGUCACACCUCACUGGCCAUCAAAGACUUCAUACUGGAGAGAAACCUUAUAUGUGUACUGAAUGUGGAAAAUCCUUCUCUCAGAAAUCACCUCUUAUCAUACACCAGAGAAUUCAUACAGGGGAGAAACCUUAUCAGUGUGGUGAAUGUGGCAAAACCUUCUCCCAGAAAUCACUCCUCAUUAUUCAUCUGAGAGUUCACACAGGGGAGAAACCUUAUGAGUGUACUGAGUGUGGGAGGGCCUUUUCCCUGAAGUCACAUCUCAUUCUACAUCAGAGAGGUCAUACUGGAGAGAAACCCUAUGAAUGUAGUGAAUGUGGAAAGGCCUUCUGUGGAAAGUCUCCACUCAUUAUACAUCAGAAAACUCAUCCUAGGGAGAAAACCCCUGAAUGUGCUGAGUCUGGAAUGACUUUUUUCUGGAAAUCACAGAUGAUUACAUAUCAGAGAAGACACACUGGGGAGAAACCCUCCAGAUGCAGUGACUGUGGGAAGGCAUUCUGCCAGCAUGUAUACUUUACUGGGCAUCAGAAUCCAUAUAGGAAAGACACCUUGUAUAUAUGCUGAUUGUGGGAAGGCCUAUUCCCAGAAGUCAGUCCUCAUUGUCUAUGGGAAAACUCACAUUGAAUAGAAAUAGUGACAACUUCUCAACUGUAGAAUAGACUAAUAUGUUCCUCAGUAUACAUGAUUACCCUUCCACAGAAUGAUCUGCUUAGGCCCUCAGAAUAUUUUCAACAUCACAAAUAUGGAAUCAAUUUGCUCACCCUCAAACUGUCUCAGCCCUCUUCACAGAAUAAAUGUAUCUGGAAGAAUUAGCACUACUUUGGUGUUGUUUGGUCAUUAAAUGCUUUAUAGAAUUCUCUUGUGAAUUUAUUUGGGCAUGGUGCAUUAUUUGAAGGGUAUCUCUUUGUCAUCUUUCUCUAUUUUUUCCAUAUUUUUCUGUUUAGAUUAUAUAUGCAUUUAUGUAUUUAUUUAUUUUGAGAUGGAGUCUCGCUCUGUUACCCAGGCUGGAGUGCAGUGGCGUGAUCUUGGCUCACUGCAACCUCCACCUCCUAGGUUUGAGCGAUUGUCCUGCCUCGCCCUCUCGAGUAGCUGGGAUUAUAGGCAUGCACCACCAGGCCCGGCUAAUUUUUGUAUUUUUAGUAGAGAUGGGGUUUCACCAUGUUGGCAAGGCUGGUCUCGAACUCCUGACCUCAGGUGAUCCACCCACUUCGGCUUCCCAAAGUGCUGGGAUUACAGGCAUGAGCCACAGCACCUGACCUAUAUAUGCAUUUAGAUUGAGAUAUUGAUAUAUCAAUAUAUAGAUGUAGAAAUAUGGACUCUUUGUAAUUUUUAAAAAUCAUGUAUUUCCUCAAGGUUCUUAAUAUAUUUGCAUAAUUUUGGGUAAAGUAGUCUCAUGAUUAAUUUCCUUUAUAUCUGUGGUUAUUUCUCCAACAUAGUUCUCAUAGAGUGUAUUUGUGAUUUUUUCCCUCAAUUAGGUAAAUAAAUGCUAAUAUUUUAUUUCUUUUACUCUCCCUCA